AUCUUUCCUUGGUGCCAACCAUGCCUGCAUAUCAGGGCAGCAUUCUAUGAUCCCAUGGCUCUCACAUCGACAGACCACAACACUAAGCCAACAAUGAUACGGCGUCCACCAGCAGUUGUUUGCUACAUUUGUGGUCGUGAAUAUGGAACAAAAUCUAUUAGCAUUCAUGAGCCACAAUGUCUGAAAAAAUGGCAUAAUGAAAACAACUUGUUGCCUAAAGAGUUAAGGAGACCAGUACCUAAAAAACCAGAAGUCAGGACCAUUACUGCCAAAGGCUUCUAUGAUCUUGAUGCUUUAAAUGAAGCUGCUUGGACAAGUGCCCACAGCCAGUUGGUUCCCUGUAAUGUUUGUGGGCGUACCUUCCUGCCAGACAGACUGAUUGUUCACCAACGAUCUUGUAAACCCAAAGCCGCCAAGUAAAGCCCUUUUCUCUCUA